ACACACAAUAGUGGACAGGAGAGAGCUCAGCUGUUGCCCGGCGCGUCCGCGGGCGGCUCGGCGGCCGGCGGGGCUGGGGAGCCUCCCGGUGAGUACCCUCGCCCGCGCCCCCUCUGGGCCUUUCUCUCCUCCGCGCCGCCGCCGCCGGUGCGCAGGCCGGCUGGGGACUCGCCUCCGCUCGGGCCUUCGGUUUCGCUCCCUCGCUGAGUCCCUUCUCCCCGCCAACAAAAGCAAAUCUCCUUGGACCGGCUGUUGGGGGAAAAAAGUGUUAGCCGUCUCUCCCGGAUCUGCAAGGGGGAAAAAAUUUGGAACCAUAAAGUUGAAAACUUUUUUCUCUCAGUUUGGAAGAAGCCCUUCGUCAUGAAUGGGAUCUGCAGAGUUCGGGCGAGAGGAGGCGAGAGGCGCAAAGGUAACAAAGCCCGGGCCCGGGCUGGCGUGUUUUGAUCGUUUUAUGAGCUCUUUUCACAACUGAAAGAAGAAACACUCUCUCGCCUCUUCCUUUUUCUUUUUUAACUUUCUUGGCUGGGUUUUUAUGGUGGAUGCUUCAGCAGGUUUGCUCCCUUUUAUGAUGACUGAUGCUUGGGUCAGAGGGAGAGAAAGAGGGGCCUCGACACCUGGAGAGUGUUUGAACUGGUUGGGACUGAGGUGUCAGGGCCCAUGAAAAACCCCAGAGAAGACGGUUGUUUUGUGAGGCAGUUCAGAAGCGCUUUUCUGGUUUUGGAAAAUGCAGGCAGGCACAGCGAGCCCCAGCAUGUGUGCAUGGGUGUGUCUAGUGAGGUCCACAUGUGGUCGGUGUGUUCCUGUGACUCUGCUUGUCUACACUGGGUACUGGUGUCCCCUAUGCCUGUUUACCAGUGAGACGUUGUCACUGCUGCCUCUUGGAAAAAUCAAAUCCAGUGCUUGGAUGGAAUGUUCCAGCUUUGGAGCGGGUAUAAGUGGAUAUGUUCUUUUUUUUCUUCUUGUGUCUAGCUUGGGAUUCUAGACAAAUAUGUGCUACUCUCUGGAGCAGGAAACUGCUCAGUUCACAGACAAGGUGGACUGAUGCAGAAAUAUUUCUCUUCUGCUCUGUCCCCCCAGCCUUCUUCCUGGAGGAGCAAUGUUGGUUUGGUUUGGUUUGGUUUCCCUUUGCUCUCCUAAUUUGAGGUCUCUGUUCUCUCCUCUGCAGCCCUGUUUCUUAGGCUGAGGGAGUCAGUGGGCUCUGCAGCCGACCUGAAUGUGUUGGCCCUUUUUCCCUGAGGCCUCACUUAGGGUUUGGAGGCGGGAGGCUGGCAGGAGAGAGAGUUCAUGGAGAGGCCACGUUUUCUAGGCGAUUAGCUCAGUAUUAGAACCACAAAAUGACCUCGGAAGCCCCUUGACCUCGCUGAGACUGGACAUUGUGUUGGCAUUUGCCUCCUGCCCAGGAGGGAGAGUCACACCUCUGCAGGGAGGGGUCCUUGGCCCAUCAUAUGUCCCAUCUUCUCCAUCCCCCUCUAGGCCCCAAACCCAUCUUUGCUAUUUUGGAAAUUUUGGAUUAUUUUUCUAUUACUGCCCACUGGGGGAAAAAAACGUAAAGAUUUUUAGCCCAAGGGUCCAGUUGGGGGACGAAAGUAGGGUGCUAAUCUGUCUCUCUGUACACAGCACCUUCAGCAGUCCAGGCUCCAGCCAUCCUCCCCGCAACCACUCCCAGGUCCAGUUCAUCUCUUUACUAUUUCACCUGGAGGGAACUGAGGGAAGAAAGACAAAGGGAGAAGAUAUGAGAGGUUGGAGGGGCCUAAUCCACAAGGCUUCAGAGGGCCAGGGGAAUAAACUCCUGGGCUGCGAGGAGAGAAAGGGCUUAUCCGCCCUGAACAUUGCUUCAGAGGCUGUCAUCUCCCUGAGGGCUGACAUCCAAAUCCACAGCCUGUCAACCCAUUUUCUGAAGUUCAUUUGUUGAGGAAGCUAUUUCUAUAACUACCUUUACCUCUUUCCCCUAAUUCUCAAUCUCCUCAAUAAUGAAAAAAGCCCUUGGAGUGCCUCACCCACCAGAGGAGCAAGGGAAAUGGGAGGAGGAUCAGUGCAGGCUAUUCUGAGUACUUUCCAGGGCCUGCUGUCCCAGGUUAGCCAAAGUUUCCAGAAACUUUUAAGAAAUAGGUGAAGGAUUUGCCAAACAGUGAGCCCUGAACAUAGAGCCUUUCCAAAAACUGUAUUCUGUUUGCUGUAUCUUAAAAAUCCACACCAGCAGCCACCCUCUUAGGGAGAGACAGAGACAAAGAGAAAGAGAAAGAGAGACAGAUACAGACAGACGCUGGCUGGGAAGAUGAAAUGUUACCCUUCAGUUAAGACUAGGAGAGACAGAACCUUGCUGGGAUAUGUGGGUUGUUGGUUUGCAUUUUGUAAAUUGUUUCUUGACAUUUGGGGACUCUAUCUCAGGCAAGAAAUAACUGGAGUGGUUGAUACUCUCUCCUUUGUCCCUGGGUGGCAUAAGUAGAGGGGCUGGAGGCCUCAGGAAAGACAGAGGAUGAGCACAAAGCUAGCUAGGCUGCUCCUGGACUAAAAAUAUAUGGGGCUCAGGGAGAUGUGUAUUCAUUACCUGUAAGGGCAGAUAGCCAGUUGUGGGCCUUCUACAGGCUCAAGUGACAAAGACCUAGUCGCCGAGGACUUUACAAACUGCUUUCUGCAAUGUGAGGAUUAGGGCCCACCAAAGGGAAAAGGAGAGAGACCAUAGUCAGGGAAGCCUGGGGUUCACUAAGGGGAACUGCCAGAUCUCCCAUUUCCUUCACUCCAGACAAUCCUAGUGCCACUCCAGUCCUCCCAACCUUUUGACUUCUUUCCCUCUUUCUCCCCAGUUCCCUCGGCCCUCCCCAUUCUCCCUCCUACUUCCACCCGCCUGUCCUGGGCAGAGGGGGUUGCCCAGUUCUGCCAGAGCCCUUGAAGGCGGCCCCAGCGCUGGCAGUGGGUCUCCCUGGGAAGCGGCAGCUGGGGAGGGGGUCUGGUUGGAAAACGGAGUUGGGAAGUUUCUCAGCGUGAGUUGAGCGCUGACGGAUUUGUGAUCAGCCAUAAAACUGGCGCGUUCAGAUUCGUAAAUCAAUCUCGCCUUUCUCACAGUGUAAACGUUCGCUUUAUCGGCAGCAAGAAAGUGCUCGGCUCGCGAUCAGGCGCUUGUUUAUUUGAACGUGGACAUUCCCAGGAUCCGAAAAGAGUAUGGUCAUUUUAACAGAACCUGCUGGCGUGCCUUCGUGUCAUUUUGCUGUUCUUUUUCUUGUCCUUAAAAAUUAUUUCUCCGUUUUAGAGAUUGCUGUCUUCCCACAUCCAGCAUUUCUCUCUCCUCUCUCUGCUCUCUCUCUAUUUUCAUUUUAGACUUUAGCAGAGUGUUUUUCUCUGGAGGACCAUUUUUAAUGGAUUUGUGGCCAGAACGUUUCAGGGAGUUGCCCUCGCUGGAGCCGGGAGCAGGGCCCACAUCGGGAUCAGGCUGAAUUCAAUACCAGUCUGUGUUUUGUAUCUGGACAAUCAAAGCUGACCACCUCCCCUACAGAGUCCAGGCCUGGCCGGCGCCCCCACCCCAUGAGGCCAGAGCAGAUUCCAGUGCUCUUAGCUGGGGCAGAAGCUGUGCAGCUGCCACUGUAGCUGGAACCUCCGAGGCCGACACCGGGGUGGCUGUUUCUUUGGGGCUUGUUAAGACAACCGGGUCCUCAACCUUCUCUCCACUGAGUUGCUUUUGGUUUAGACCCCUUCGAACAAGCCGGGGGAGGCCCCUCAGACCCCUGCUCCCGUACCCUGAAGCUCAUUCUUCCUGGAUUCCCUGCCUGCCCCGGAGGCUGUGGUCCUGGCUGCCUCCAGAGCUGCUGAGGACAGAUAAGGCUGCGACUUCUUCAGGAAUGUCUUUUCUGCUUCCCUUUGCAUCCCCACCCCCCAUCCCAUGCCCCGGCCGAGAACUCUGAUUCUAGUUGCACGUAACUGGUCAAGUUUGGAUGGGGGGUUGUUUUUGUUUUAUUUUGUUUAUAUUUGAGUUGAAGGGGUCUGUGUGUGUCUCUCUCUUUAGGCCUGGGGAAUAGAUAGUCCCUGGUAUUUAACCCUUUAACAGGCAUAGCCAUCCCCCAUCUUUUUCCCACUGAUCAGCCUCCAUUGUUUGUUGAUUGGAAGCUCGGGGUGCUAACACCUGGGAAAUAGGGAUCCUGGGGCUGCCAGGCUGACUUCAAAGCUUUUCUUUUCUUUUCCCUCCUCUCCUGUUCAAAUCUCCAGCUGUCUUCACUGGUGGGUUUGGGAAGGGGGGGAAAUGAGACAGGGUGUGACAUAGGUAGAGAGAGGCUGACAGUCCGAUUCUUUUGUGUAGAAACCUUAGUCCCAGUCUUUGUCUCUAGAAUCUAUUUUCAAACGGUCAGUCGCAUUUGAUUUCCUAUAGUAGUAACAACACAACAGGGAAAAAAGUCCCCCUUGCGGUUAUUCUCAACUCUGGAAGCUCCAGAGUAAUCUCUUCACCCUGUCCCUUUUUUGCCCCUUCAAAAGGUACCAGAAAAGAUCAAAACGAGAAUAAAGCCAGAAGCCCCAUUAUUUAUCCACUUAUACCAUGGACUUAUGAAGUGUUUAUUUUCAAAGUGGCUCCUUCAGAAAUUUUGUCCAUUAUUUAGGAAGAGAGGGAGUGGGUCUCACUCAAGUAAAUAUCCCCAGGAGUUGGGGAAAAAAUGGAGUUGGGGAGGGAACCUUAAUCCUAAAGGAUGCAGAGAGAAGAACUGGAAGCUGAGAAAUCCAGGGGCUUGGAGAAGGGCUCUGAGCCCACCCCACCCCCACCCCCUAGACGCCCCUGCAGACUAUUUCUGCACCUCCACGAACUAAGCAGAAGCAGGAGGAGAAGGGAGAGAGGAGAGGUGGGCUGUGGGUAAGUGUGUGUCCAUGGGGGUUAGGGAGCUGCAGAUGUAGUAGGUAUGGAUGUGAGUGUGGGAGACAGACGGAGACCUCACUACUGUUCCAUUGGUGGGUUGAGGGGGAACUUAUUUUGCAGGAAAAUUUCUCCUCCUGAAGGGGAAGGUCAUAGUGGUCCUUUGAGCCUGAAAUCGAAAGACCCCCUUCCCCCUCCCGGUCACGUGAUUCAUUAAAUAAUUAAUGCCGAGGUUGCAGAAUAGAUAUGUAUUCGUCAGGAAAAUCGCAGGCUCGGUCUCCCUGUUUCUGACGUGCAAUUCAACUGUCCUUUGAAAAACAAGCCUGUACCCCGAGAAAAAAAAAGAGAGGGGGGAGAGAGAGAGGGAGAGAGAGAGAGAGAAAGAAAGGGAGACAGCAAUAAAACAGCCCCGCAGCCGGAGCCACACCGCGGGCUGGGGUAUUGUAAGUAGAAGGGAUUUCUCACUACCUACCGCGUCUUAUAUGUCCAUGUAAAUUUAUUGUUUGUUAUUAAUGUUAUUGUCGUAAAAUGUGACAAAUAGCCAUCUUCAUUUCCUGCCAUUUCUCUUCACACGGUGCUCUGUGUGUUUAUGCCCAUUGAGGCAUUGCAUAGAGAUUUUAGGAAUAUUCUUCUUUUCUCUCUCUCUCUUUCUCCCUCCCUCCCUCUCCCUCUCUCCCUCUGUCCUCCAACCUUUUUCUUGAUUUAUAGCAAUAUGGGUGUCAGCUUCUCAGCCGGCAUGCCAGCCAUUGUGUGUGUGUGUGUCCGCGCGUGUGUGUGCGUGCGCGUCUGCGUGUGUUUGUGAGCGAGUUGUGUUGUUUAUGGCCAUGUCUUCGAUAAAUCAUUUUUCACGGAAAAUGAUGUGGAAGCUGGGCUGUUUCUGCGGCCGGCCGGGAGAGAGUCGCUCUCGGAGGCACUUCCUCCCUCUCUGCUCUGCUCCCAGGAGUUGGUUAUUUCAGACGAUUUACAGUAAUAUAUCAGCAGUUAAUAUGAAAGCUCUAUAGCUGGAGGUCUUAAAUUACAGCAUCUGUGAUUAUCAAUUAAAGCGAGAUUUUCAUAAAUUUGGUAAACCAGAAAUGCCUCAUUGGCAUAUAAACCCAGUCAAUGACCAUGGUCUAAUAUAAAAAUUAUAUUUGUGAGCCUGAUAGAGCCAACAUUCCUGCAGCAGCAGACAGAGCUCCAUUUUUUAGCAGCUCCCCUCCAGGAGUUUGGCUUCUCCAACUCCAGCCCUGGAUGAACAAACCCAACUCUGAAGGCAGAAGGAGCCUUAGAGUAAGAGAGGUGGAAGUGGAGAAAGAAAUUACUGGAGUUGAAGGCAAAUAUUUUUGUGAUCAAUGGAGACCAAAUCAAAGUUCUGUGCAAUUGGAAAGGGAUGGGAGGGGUUCCGUUACAUUAUUAAAGCUUAAUUUAUAGGACUGAUGUGUCUGGGGGGUGGUCAAAGGUGGAAAAGGAAUCACCCAAAUUGGGGGAGACAAUGGAGGCAAGCAGAGGGUGAAGGGCAGGGAGAGAAGCUGAAAGCUUUGGCUCCCCACCCUCCUGGCUAACAAAACAAGGAAAUGAAUUCACACCCCAGGAGCCUUCCUUUGACCUGCUGAAACAAAGAAAAGUUUCCUCAGCAGUGAGGGACUCUGUGUUUGGGGCUAAAGUGGGGAGAAGUUCUCCGAAGUUUUUCUAGAAAAGAAAUGUUCUAGGAAUCAGGUGGUCCCAGAAAGUUGGGAGUGUUGGAGGAUGUUGGGUGUGUUCUUUUAACUAAGUCCCCAUCCAAAAAGGGAGCAAACGGGGUGCAGAUUGGAGAGGGAGGGGAAGAGCUGUUAACUUUCUCCUAUAGUUUCAUGUGGAGGUCACAGUUCCUUCCUACUAGGGGAGAGGCUGCUGGUCAAGAGCAAAGCCAGAGGUGGCUUUGGGGAAUGUUCUGCACUGUGCCCCAAAGUUGUGAUGGAUGAGGUGCAGAGGGCCAGAGCCUUCACCAACUCCAGUCCCAGCUGUUGGCCCCUCAUUCCCUGACUGGAGCCAGGCCAACUGACUUUAUAGCCACGAUUAUCUGUGAUAUUUAACUCUGCCUGCUAGUGUAAACCUUUGAGCAGGGAAGUUAGAGCAACGCCGCGCCCAGGUGUUAAUUAUUCAUGGCAUCCACUACGUGGAGUGGCAGCUUAGGCCCCAGUCCCUGCAGCAUCCAGGAGCUCGCUCCCACACUCUGCUCCAAGUGAACACUGAGUCUCAUCCAUGUUAACAAGGGAUUCUCAGUGGGUAGUGGGUGAAGCCUCCCAAUUCAGGAGUCUCAGUUGAAAAGGGUUUGGGGAGAAAGAGAAGGCCAGGACCCAAGGCUGGGAUGGGUAGAGGCACUGUCUGACCUGGAUAAAAAGAACUAGGGAAAAGUCUGGAUACAGGGGCAGCUUUGACAGCACUGGAGAUUGUGAGGAGGUGGGAAGGGCUGGCAGAGGCAGCAAAGAGACCUGGGGCAUAGGGGCUCCAAACCUUUCAGUCUCAUUCCCCACCCACUCCUUGAGUGUUGGAGAAUCCCACACACAUUCAGUGUGAGAGGCAAGCAGUUCUACUUCUCCCUCAUCUGGAAAGUGUUGGGGGGUAUGACUGUGAAGAGGGUGCGUUCUCCCUCAAACCGGUGGUCCAGAGUUAGGGCAAAGUCUUGGAGUUUUUGAGAGAGCAGGGAAGGAUCACUUCUUCCAUGGGGAGGAGGAGGGACAUGACAGAGAAGGAAGAGGGUAGAAUCAUUUGUAUUAGCUUCUGAAUUCAGCAUGCUUUGAAAGAUGGGAAAGAAAAGGAUCUGCUCUUUGGGCCAGCCCAUAGCUAGCAUGGAGAGCCAGUCCCACAGGCCCCUUCCCCCUGCGUUUGCAACUCCUCCUCCCCAACCCUUUUCCAUCUCCCCUCCUGCUGCUACCUUUGCCUGUGACGUGGAAGUCUGACCAACCACCCCCACCCCCACUCCACCAGCUUUUCCUCUUUAUUCUUUCAGCCCUCUUCAGGUCUUUGUCUCCUCUGGCCCAGAGGAGAGGAGGUGACACUGAUACCCCCUCCCCUUCCCUUUCCCCAACACGCACAGACUCUUCCCCAGGAGACAAAGCAAGGGGACCAUCCCUUGCCACCAUUAUCUGGUAAAUCCCCCAUGUGAUGCCUAAUGCCUUCCAUCCAGGCAUCUAGGCCUACCCCAAAUCAGCAAGUUUGAAAGGACUUUGUUGUUUAUAUAUACAUUUGCUUCAUUUAGCUAUGAAGCACCCUGUCUCUUACCAGUCCUGCACCCUCCACCCCACUGAUUUGCUUUUGUGUUGUUCAGGGGUUGGGAUAGAAUGCAUCUGGUAGACAGAGCUCUAAGAAAGCUGCUGACUCUGUCUUCUCCCCUAACUCUCUGCUGGUAUCCUCUCUAUAUAAUUGCAGUGUUUAUCUCUGUGCCUUUAAGGAGGCAGGCUGCUAACGCUUUAGUGACCAGAGGAAUUGGAUAGAAAGAUGAAGAGUGAGAUGAGGAAGAGAGGGACCCAGAGAGAGAACAAGCAGCAGGAUCCCUUUCUGGGAUGGGAAGUCAAGGCUGAGCCCAAGGAGGUGAUGACAGGGAGAGUGGAAACAAAGGCCAGUCAGAGGGGAAGGGAGGCUGUCCUGGAGGAAGGAGCCCCACAAUUCACAAGGGGACACACACACAGAGUUAAGUGAGAACAAGGGCAGUGGGAAGGAAACUACCCCUUUUGUCCCCUUCUCUCUAGAAGAGAAUUUCUCUGGAUAGAGGGUGGGUUCCCCCACAGAGGAAAGGGAAGAAGAGACUCAACCUAAUGGGUGAGCCCAGAAGUGAUUUCUGGAGACACUCCUAAAUCCUUUGCAAGGCUCAAUUCAAAUUCACUGAAGACACUGAGAGACGCAGAAUUGGAAAAAGACAAAGGGGCUGUGAGAAAGGAACGGAGACAACAGAGAUGGUUAGAAAAGACAGAGAGACCCAACACAGAAAAAAAGCCCAAACCCUUUGGGGAGCAGGCACAGAGGGAAGCCCCUCCAGGCUCCCUGCUCCCUAGCAGCCUUCUUUACAGGAAGCUGCCCAAAGCCCAGGCCAUCUCAGAAACAACUGCCUCUAGAGUAGGCCCUUGGGGGUGCUAAAUCAGGUGUGAGGCAGCUGUGGCAGGAGCUGAAGUGCCAGGGAAUGGCCAAGAUGUCCAGGACACUUCAGCCUCCACCACAAUCACCAGCAUCAGUAACUUAAUCAUUGGGACCUCCCCAAACAGAAUUUCAUCAUGGGGGUGGGGGGAGUUGGGACUUUCACACCUGGACCCUGGAAUCCUUUCUUGGCUUUUCUUCCCCCUUGUGGGUUUGGUCUCUUUUUUUCUCUAGGGACCUGGGGAAGUUGUUGAUCUUCCAGCCGCCUAAGAACUUUCACCUCCAUUCCACAUCUCCUCCCUCAAACUCCCAGCCUUAACAAGCGGAUGCUUCCCCUACUAAUCUCCUUCCUCCCCCAUCUUACAGGAAAGAACAAGAAAAGGAAAAAGAGAAAGCAAGUUCCUACCAGCCUAAGCAGCUUUAGAAAACUCGAGGGAAAAGGGGAGAUGCAAAUCUUUCUCGCCCGUCUGAUCCUUCCUAUUGCCCCCUCGCCAUUGCUCUGUUCCCUCCAUUGCCGCCCUCCCUGUCCCCACUCCUGUCCUGCCCAGAACUCUCUCCCUUCCCCUCCCUUCUCUGCCGGGUCGGACAUAUGGAACCCAUUUCGCUGGUGACAUUGAAGAGUCGCCGGUGUGCCCGCCUUCCGCCAUGGCGCCCCCGGCGCUCCCUACGCCUCGCCGUGCCCCUGUCAGUUGCCGCUCCUCUCGCCUGGCAACUUGGCCCGCUCUCAAAGCCCGAGUUCAGCUCGGUGCCAGACGAGCCCGGGGUUCCCGCAGCCCUGCGCGGCCCGGACGGAGUGGGAGCUUCUCAGGAAACUGGCGUCUGCCGCGCCCGGAGUGCCAGAUCCGCGCGCUCCUGGGGCCCUGGAGGCCGAACAAAGCCGGGGGCGGGGGCGGGGGCGGGGUGGGGGCGAGCGCAUCCGGGCCUCUCCCCCAGCUCGGCGGGACGCUCGGGGGUUGCUGGGGGUUGCUGCGGGUUGAGCGACUAGGAUGCGGCUGGCUGCGGCGGCGGAGCCCCAGCCUGGGCCGAGGGUCCGGGGCCUGGCAGUCGGCCCCCGCGCGCACCCAGCGCCCGGCCGCCCGCCGUUGCCCGCGCCCUAGCGGAAGACCGCACAGGAGGGGAGAUUUGUCGCCUGCCGCUCGCUCUGGGGCUCGAUGUGAAUAUAUAUUAUGUCUGCCUGUUCUCCCCUCGUCGGUGGCUAAGGCCGCCACGCACCUGGAGGGCGACUACCAGCGCUCAGCUUGCUCGCUGCAGUCCCUGGGCAACGCUGCCCCACAUGCCAAGAGCAAGGAGCUCAACGGCAGCUGCAUGAGGCCGGGUCUGGCCCCCGAGCCCCUGUCGGCCCCGCCUGGCUCACCCCCGCCCAGUGCCGCACCUACCAGUGCCACUAGCAACAGCAGUAAUGGGGGCGGGCCCAGCAAAAGUGGUCCCCCAAAGUGCGGUCCCGGCACCAACUCCACCCUCACCAAACAGAUAUUCCCCUGGAUGAAAGAGUCGAGGCAAACGUCCAAGCUGAAAAACAACUCCCCCGGCACAGCAGAGGGCUGUGGUGGCGGCGGCGGUGGCGGCGGCGGCGGAGGCAGUGGUGGCAGCGGGGGCGGUGGCGGCGGCGGCGGGGGAGGGGACAAGAGCCCCCCGGGGUCGGCGGCGUCCAAGCGGGCGCGGACGGCGUACACGAGCGCGCAGCUGGUGGAGCUGGAGAAGGAGUUCCAUUUUAACCGCUACCUGUGCCGGCCUCGCCGUGUAGAGAUGGCCAACCUGCUGAACCUCAGCGAGCGGCAGAUCAAGAUCUGGUUCCAGAACCGGCGCAUGAAGUACAAGAAGGACCAGAAGGCCAAGGGAUUGGCCUCGUCGUCGGGGGGCCCAUCUCCAGCCGGCAGCCCCCCGCAGCCCAUGCAGUCCACGGCCGGCUUCAUGAACGCCUUACACUCCAUGACCCCCAGCUACGAGAGCCCGUCCCCACCCGCCUUCGGUAAAGCCCACCAGAAUGCCUACGCGCUGCCCUCCAACUACCAGCCCCCUCUCAAAGGCUGCGGCGCCCCGCAGAAGUACCCUCCGACCCCGGCGCCCGAGUAUGAGCCGCACGUCCUCCAAGCCAACGGGGGCGCCUACGGGACGCCCACCAUGCAGGGCAGUCCGGUGUACGUGGGCGGGGGCGGCUACGCGGAUCCGCUGCCGCCCCCUGCCGGCCCCUCCCUCUAUGGCCUCAACCACCUUUCCCAUCACCCUUCCGGGAACCUGGACUACAACGGGGCGCCCCCUAUGGCGCCCAGCCAGCACCACGGACCCUGCGAACCCCACCCCACCUACACAGACCUCUCCUCUCACCACGCGCCUCCUCCUCAGGGUAGAAUCCAAGAAGCGCCCAAAUUAACACACCUGUGAUGGGAAAGGGCGAACGAGGAUUAGGGGAUGGGGAGGAAGAGAGAGACUGUGGAGCUCUGGGGGGCAACCUGGAGGUCUGAAAAGAGGAGCCAGAGAAGGUGGUACCCAGGCUUCCUGGUCAGAACCGGCCUGGAGCUCCUUCCCUUCCCCCUGGCCUGAGAGGUUGCUUUUAAGUCUUCCACCCCUUGUUCCAUCUGCCUGCCAACCCAUCGGAAAGGAAUCCACAUCAUAUUGGAGAUGACCCCAUCAACCCCAGGGCUCCAGCACUACCAAGUUGGAAUUCCACGCCCGGGAGUGGGGUAGAGGAAGACGAGACAGGACGAGGCAGAAAAGCACAUUUUAAAAACCAGACAAGAUGGCUAGGCCAUCACCAACCAACGGACUUACCUUACAUCUUUGUAGGUAAUUCCCCCCAAAUCUUGAUUUUUUUUUUUCCUCAAUUAUCCUUUAAAAAAUAAGAAAACACAUUUCAAACCCAAAAGGCACAAAACACGUUCCCUUCCAACUUUCCCAAAACCUCAAAUUUGUUCCCAUUUGAGGUUUAUUGAGGUACACUUCUAGCCCCCGGUUUUUCUGCUCUAGAACAUUCAUAUCUAUACAUCCCACCCCCAUCAAUUACAGUUUUUAGAGGGCUCAGGGAUGGUGAGAGAUCCUGAAAGAGCUGCCUAUAUUAUAAAUUAUAUACAUUUUUUUUUAAGGAAAAGUGUGGAGGCUAGGGCAGGCAGGUUGUUAGGACUGAAGGUUUGCCCAUUCUGCUGCCUCCAUCUCAGCUCCAGCUCCAUCCCCCUCUCCACAGAAAGCAGUUGGUGACACGAGGUUCUAUACUUUUCUUCUGUUGCUCUCUUGACUUAACGUGAAAACAGGGUAUAUUUGAACAAACUGUCCCAGGCAGGGGCUGGGCAGGGCCUGUGUGCCUUGCUCAGCCUCCUGACAGGACACUUUUGUUGCACUUAGAAUUUACAUUUUAAUGGAUGUAAAAACAACUGUGAGAGAUGUCUGGGCCUGCAGAAGUCCAGCAUUGCUCAAAAAAGCGUGUGUUCUAGUGAACAUUUUCAUAUAUAUUUAUUGGUUAUAGCCUGUUAAAAUAUUUUCUUUUUUGUAUUAUUUAUCCCCCUACAUUAUGUAUUUAUAUGAGGGAAAAAAAGGAAAAAAUUGUACUUUUUUAGUAUUUACCUGUUACAAAGGACAUUGUGUUUCCUGUCAUGUAAAACCAGCUAUUUUAGUUACUAUUGUACUCUAGAAAAGAGCUGUAGAUUUAUGUUAAACUCGUACUUACGAACAAUUGUAAUUAGUUCUAAAAGGCAUGAACUCAGCUCCUAAUCGUCACUGUAUAGUCCUGAAUUUGUAGAACUAGAGUUAAUUCCCUCUUGGAACUUUCUUUGUUCUUCAGUAGUUACUUUUUUCCUUACCUAAAAGGGUUGUCUGUCAAACAAUUCUUGAAUAAACUUUCUGUUAUCAAUUUUA